GGCGCUUUGGCUGUCAUAGGUGCGGCUGACUGCACAGAAGUCACUGGGGCCUUUGACUUCUACACACUCCCUGUGGGGCUCCGCACUGUGCCCGUCACCGAGAGCCAGUGGGAUGGUGAUUGCUCACACCAAAGCCUUGGACCCCUCCCAGCCUGUGACCUUUGUGACCAACUCCACCUACGCAGCAGACAAGGGGGCUCUGUAUGUGGAUGUGAUCCGUGUGAACAGCUACUACUCUUGGUAUCGCAACUACGGGCACCUGGAGUUGAUUCAGCUGCAGCUGGCCGCCCAGUUUGAGAACUGGUGUAAGACAUCACAAUCCCAUUAUUCAGAGCGAGUAUGGAGUGGAAACGCUUGUAGGGUUUCACCAGGGCUGGUGAAUUACCAGAUCUCCGUCAAGUGCAGUAACCAGUUCAAGUUGGAAGUGUGUCUUUUGAAAUCAGAAAACAAAGUCGUGGACAACCAGGCUGGGACCCAGGGCCAGCUGAAGGUGCUGGGUGCCAACCUCUGGUGGCCGUACCUGAUGCACGAACACCCCGCCUACCUGUACUCGUGGGAGGAUGGUGAUUGCUCACACCAAAGCCUUGGACCCCUCCCAGCCUGUGACCUUUGUGACCAACUCCACCUACGCAGCAGACAAGGGGGGCUGGUGAAUUACCAGAUCUCCGUCAAGUGCAGUAACCAGUUCAAGUUGGAAGUGUGUCUUUUGAAAUCAGAAAACAAAGUCGUGGACAACCAGGCUGGGACCCAGGGCCAGCUGAAGGUGCUGGGUGCCAACCUCUGGUGGCCGUACCUGAUGCACGAACACCCCGCCUACCUGUACUCGUGGGAGGAUGGUGAUUGCUCACACCAAAGCCUUGGACCCCUCCCAGCCUGUGACCUUUGUGACCAACUCCACCUACGCAGCAGACAAGGGGGGCUGGUGAAUUACCAGAUCUCCGUCAAGUGCAGUAACCAGUUCAAGUUGGAAGUGUGUCUUUUGAAAUCAGAAAACAAAGUCGUGGACAACCAGGCUGGGACCCAGGGCCAGCUGAAGGUGCUGGGUGCCAACCUCUGGUGGCCGUACCUGAUGCACGAACACCCCGCCUACCUGUACUCGUGGGAGGAUGGUGAUUGCUCACACCAAAGCCUUGGACCCCUCCCAGCCUGUGACCUUUGUGACCAACUCCACCUACGCAGCAGACAAGGGGGGCUGGUGAAUUACCAGAUCUCCGUCAAGUGCAGUAACCAGUUCAAGUUGGAAGUGUGUCUUUUGAAAUCAGAAAACAAAGUCGUGGACAACCAGGCUGGGACCCAGGGCCAGCUGAAGGUGCUGGGUGCCAACCUCUGGUGGCCGUACCUGAUGCACGAACACCCCGCCUACCUGUACUCGUGGGAGGAUGGUGAUUGCUCACACCAAAGCCUUGGACCCCUCCCAGCCUGUGACCUUUGUGACCAACUCCACCUACGCAGCAGACAAGGGGGCUCUGUAUGUGGAUGUGAUCCGUGUGAACAGCUACUACUCUUGGUAUCGCAACUACGGGCACCUGGAGUUGAUUCAGCUGCAGCUGGCCGCCCAGUUUGAGAACUGGUGUAAGACAUCACAAUCCCAUUAUUCAGAGCGAGUAUGGAGUGGAAACGCUUGUAGGGUUUCACCAG